ACUUUCUUUUGUAAAUGUGGUUUCUACAAAGAUGAAACUACUAAAACUUACAGGUUUUAUUUUUUUCUUGUUUUUUUUGACUGAAUCCCUAACCCUGCCCACACAACCUCGGGAUAUAGAGAACUUCAAUAGUACUCAAAAAUUUAUAGAAGAUAAUAUUGAAUACAUCACCAUCAUUGCAUUUGCUCAGUAUGUUCAGGAAGCAACCUUUGAAGAAAUGGAAAAGCUGGUGAAAGACAUGGUAGAAUACAAAGACAGAUGUAUGGCUGACAAGACGCUCCCAGAGUGUUCAAAAUUACCUAAUAAUGUUUUACAGGAAAAAAUAUGUGCUAUGGAGGGGCUGCCACAAAAGCAUAAUUUCUCACACUGCUGCAGUAAGGUUGAUGCUCAAAGAAGACUCUGUUUCUUCUAUAACAAGAAAUCUGAUGUGGGAUUUCUGCCUCCUUUCCCUACCCUGGAUCCCGAAGAGAAAUGCCAGGCUUAUGAAAGUAACAGAGAAUCCCUUUUAAAUCACUUUUUAUAUGAAGUUGCCAGAAGGAACCCAUUUGUCUUCGCCCCUACACUUCUAACUGUUGCUGUUCAUUUUGAGGAGGUGGCCAAAUCAUGUUGUGAAGAACAAAACAAAGUCAACUGCCUUCAAACAAGGGCAAUACCUGUCACACAAUAUUUAAAAGCAUUUUCUUCUUAUCAAAAACAUGUCUGUGGGGCACUUUUGAAAUUUGGAACCAAAGUUGUACACUUUAUAUAUAUUGCGAUACUCAGUCAAAAAUUCCCCAAGAUUGAAUUUAAGGAGCUUAUUUCUCUUGUAGAAGAUGUUUCUUCCAACUAUGAUGGAUGCUGUGAAGGGGAUGUUGUGCAGUGCAUCCGUGACACGAGCAAGGUUAUGAACCAUAUUUGUUCAAAACAAGAUUCUAUCUCCAGCAAAAUCAAAGAGUGCUGUGAAAAGAAAAUACCAGAGCGCGGCCAGUGCAUAAUUAACUCAAACAAAGAUGAUAGACCAAAGGAUUUAUCUCUAAGAGAAGGAAAAUUUACUGACAGUGAAAAUGUGUGUCAAGAACGAGAUGCUGACCCAGACACCUUCUUUGCGAAGUUUACUUUUGAAUACUCAAGGAGACAUCCAGACCUGUCUAUACCAGAGCUUUUAAGAAUUGUUCAAAUAUACAAAGAUCUCCUGAGAAAUUGCUGCAACACAGAAAACCCUCCAGGUUGUUACCGUUACGCGGAAGACAAAUUCAAUGAGACAACUGAGAAAAGCCUCAAGAUGGUACAACAAGAAUGUAAACAUUUCCAGAAUUUGGGGAAGGAUGGUUUGAAAUACCAUUACCUCAUCAGGCUCACGAAGAUAGCUCCCCAACUCUCCACUGAAGAACUGGUGUCUCUUGGCGAGAAAAUGGUGACAGCUUUCACUACUUGCUGUACGCUAAGUGAAGAGUUUGCCUGUGUUGAUAAUUUGGCAGAUUUAGUUUUUGGAGAGUUAUGUGGAGUAAAUGAAAAUCGAACUAUCAACCCUGCUGUGGACCACUGCUGUAAAACAAACUUUGCCUUCAGAAGGCCCUGCUUUGAGAGUUUGAAAGCUGAUAAAACAUAUGUGCCUCCACCUUUCUCUCAAGAUUUAUUUACCUUUCACGCAGACAUGUGUCAAUCUCAGAAUGAGGAGCUUCAGAGGAAGACAGACAGGUUUCUUGUCAACUUAGUGAAGCUGAAGCAUGAACUCACAGAUGAAGAGCUGCAGUCUUUGUUUACAAAUUUCGCAAAUGUAGUGGAUAAGUGCUGCAAAGCAGAGAGUCCUGAAGUCUGCUUUAAUGAAGAGAGUCCAAAAAUUGGCAACUGAAGCCAGCUGCUGGAGAUAUGUAAAGAAAAAAGCACCAAAGGGAAGGCUUCCUAUCUGUGUGGUGAUGAAUCGCAUUUCCUGAGAACAAAAUAAAAGGAUUUUUCUGUAACUGUCACCUGAAAUAAUACAUUGCAGCAAGCAAUAAACACAACAUUUUGUAAAGUUA